ACUGCGGAGGAGCCGAACACUGACCGCGCCGUCCCCGCCAGGCUCCCGCGCGGCCGGCACCGCGGCCCUGAGCGCAGGCGGCCCCGGGUCUCAGGCCUCAGGCGGACCGCGCCCCGGGCUCGCAGCCCUCCCGCCCCGGCUGCCGGGCUACGGGGCAGAUGGACUCGGAGCGCCCCGCCGGUGAGUAGCUACGACCCCCGAGGCCACCUCCCGCGAACCGCUCGGCGGCAGGAGUACGUGACCAAGGGUGGGGGCGUUGGCCCAGCAGCCGAAGGGGUCUUCAGCGCGCCCAGACCCCUCGGGGCUGCGGGGCGGAAGCCGGGGCGUGACUUCCGGCGCCGCCGGGUGUGGGGCGGAGGUGUGGGGCGGCUUCCGGAGAACCCAGCGGCGCGGGACUGGGGCGGGACUUCCGGCGACACCGGAAGUGCAUUAGCGCCAGGUUGGGGUUGUGGGGUCGCGUCAGUGCGGAGACAGCGGUGUCCUGCGCGUCUUCGGGUCAGUACGGGGGGCCGCGUCGUAGGGACUCACUGGCGGUGCGCGACCUGGGCUGGCUCCGGGGGUGGCGGGCGCAGCUGCUGUGACAGCUUAUUGCAGGAGUGACCAGGACACUACCUCCUAGAAGUAAUGCCCACAGAAAGCGCAAGUUGUUCGACUGCUCGCCAAACAAAACAGAAGCGCAAAUCCCAUAGCCUUUCUAUACGAAGAACUAACAGCUCGGAGCAGGAGAGGACGGGACUGCCAAGAGACAUGUUAGAAGGACAAGAUUCUAAACUGCCUUCCUCGGUUCGCAGUACACUUCUGGAACUGUUUGGUCAAAUAGAAAGAGAAUUUGAAAACCUUUAUAUCGAAAACUUAGAAUUACGUAGAGAAAUCGACACUCUUAAUGAACGUUUAGCUGCUGAAGGACAAGCGAUUGAUGGAGCAGAGCUGAGUAAGGGCCAACUCAAAACAAAAGCCAGUCACAGCACCAGCCAGCUCUCCCAGAAACUGAAGACCACUUACAAGGCUUCCACCAGCAAGAUUGUCUCCAGCUUUAAGACCACGACAUCGAGAGCUGCCUGCCAGCUCGUGAAGGAGUACAUCGGCCACCGGGACGGCAUCUGGGAUGUCAGCGUGGCCAAGACACAGCCAGUGGUGCUCGGGACUGCAUCAGCCGAUCACACGGCUUUGCUGUGGAGCAUAGAGACAGGGAAGUGCCUAGUCAAGUACGCAGGCCACGUGGGCUCAGUAAAUUCUAUCAAAUUUCAUCCCUCAGAGCAGUUGGCUCUCACUGCUUCUGGAGAUCAGACUGCUCAUAUCUGGAGAUACGCGGUGCAGCUGCCGACACCCCAGCCUGUUGCUGACACUAGUAUAUCUGGGGAAGAUGAAGUAGAGUGCUCUGACAAGGACGAGCCCGACCUCGAUGGGGAUGUGUCCAGCGACUGCCCCACCAUCCGCGUCCCACUGACAUCCCUCAAGAGCCACCAGGGCGUGGUCAUCGCCUCCGACUGGCUGGUUGGGGGGAAGCAGGCUGUGACUGCCUCCUGGGACCGGACGGCAAACCUGUACGACGUGGAGACGUCCGAGCUCGUUCACUCUCUGACAGGGCACGACCAGGAGUUGACGCACUGCUGCACACACCCCACCCAGCGGCUCGUGGUGACCUCCUCCCGUGACACGACUUUCCGCCUCUGGGAUUUCAGGGACCCCUCCAUCCACUCGGUGAAUGUUUUCCAGGGACACACGGACACUGUGACUUCUGCCGUGUUCACCGUGGGAGACAACGUGGUUUCAGGCAGCGAUGACCGCACGGUGAAAGUCUGGGACUUGAAAAAUAUGAGAUCCCCCAUUGCAACUAUUCGCACGGACUCUGCCAUUAACAGGAUCAAUGUAUGUGUCGGCCAAAAAAUCAUAGCCCUCCCCCAUGACAACCGACAAGUGAGACUGUUUGAUAUGUCAGGAGUGCGCCUGGCGCGGCUUCCCCGGAGCAGCCGACAGGGCCACAGGAGAAUGGUAUGCUGCUCGGCAUGGAGUGAAGACCACCCCGUGUGCAAUCUGUUCACCUGUGGGUUUGACCGGCAAGCCAUUGGUUGGAACAUCAACAUCCCUGCAUUGCUACAAGAAAAAUAAGGACACCGGCAGCCCUUAGUUUCACUGUUUGCCAGCACAGACCUUUGAUGGGUGCAGGCUUUUCUGCGUAUUAAUCAGCCAUUUUUGUGAGAGUUUGACCCUGGAAAGGGUGCUUUGUAUAUGUUCUUUUCACAUAGUGCCCAGCUUGCAUGAAAUGUACAGAGAAAUGUGUGGUCGUAUUUUUUACUUUUGUCUUGUAUAUGUAUGUAUAUUGGGUCCUCUGGGCAGUAGAGGCAAAGCUCACCUCCCAUGUAGCACAUGAAAUGCUUGUGAGUUGUUGACAUUGGACAGGUGAACAGUAGGGCAUUACAUUUGUGUGAAUUAAAUGUGAACUUCUGUAUUACGUUGCGGCGUCGGCAGUCCUGCGUUCCCUGGAGUAACUGUACGUAUCUGCCUUUGCUGGGAAGACUGUGGGGCUGCCUGUGUUGGCUGGCGACCAGCAGGAUUGCUCCAGGAUUUUGUGUUUACCUCGCGUGAAGUUCAGCACGUGCUGUCGUGUAGUCAGCUUCUACUCUAAUUUCUGUUACAGUUCUGCAAAGGUAACCUGGAGUUUAGAAGUUAAAAAAAAGCAUGGGAUGUUGGAUUUGCACCAUUUGGAGUUUCUUUAGGAAAGAAAAGUUUUCUGCUUUUUUAUAGAAAAUCAUUUCAGUCUCCCGAGGUCUCAUGCUAGCAAAUUUUGAAAUAGGAUUCUAAUCACUGAUUUCAAAUAUUAAGCAAAAUGUAAAGCACUUUAAUUUAUAGCUAUGGUUAUAAACAGGUUUUAGAUGUUUCAAAUGACUUGUCCACUGAAUGUCACUUGACCUUGAUAAGAGGCCGCCUGCACACAGAGCCCAGUUAAUUCUCCGCACCUCGGUUGUGUGCUUCCGAAUGGGCUCACUCCCGUGGUGGUGUUUGAGAGCCAACAACACUACCUCAGAGACGGGUCUUUGGGAAACUUUGGGUCUCACUGUUGCCUGGCUGGAGCACUUUGGUUUAUAGCUGGAAUACUGAGUUCAGUUCAGAAGGCAGGAAAGACAGUCACACCGACGUGUCCUGAAGGUGUAGGCUCUCCACUUAGGCGCACAAGCUGACGGCUGCAGCCAGCAGGCCCCGGUGACGAGACACUUCCAGGUCUUGUGGUGGGGACGCCUCUCAGUGCCAGUCCCGCCACUGCUGAGUGAGCCUGGUGUUCUUGCCUUCUUGGAAAUUACUGCUCACCUGGUAUCUGUACGUUAAUGUUUCUUGCUGAGUUACAGUUUUGAUAAAGAGGCUCUCAUUUCCUGUGUCUUGUAUAUUCAGUCCUUUCAAUACGUCCACCUGGAGGCUCACCACUUGGAGAGACACAGGAAGGUAAUAUUUACAGCUGUCAUGUGACAUCCCCAGGUCUUUGUGUUUUGCCCUGUUUUACGGUGAGGUAGGAGGGAACCCAUCUGGGGACCGGUAGGUGCAGGUGCAGUAGGACGUGGGACUUUUGGACCCGUCCUUUGGUGCAGCUCGCCAGGGAUGAGAGGCACCUCCCUACUUGGGUCUUCAGGAGCUGGUCCAAGGAGCUUCGAAUCUAAGUCAUCUAGAAUGACCCUGAAAUGACUGACAGCCCCGGGCCCAAGAAAAACCCAUAACCACCUCAGAUGGAUCUGACGUGGCUAAGGGACAAACAGCAAAUAUUUCAGUCAUUUUGAUUUUACAAAUAAAAAAUGUGUUGUGUUUUUGUCCGACAUUAUUUCCUGACUGCACUGUUCUGAGAAUGGAGUCCACCUGGUCCCUCUGGUUGAUUAGAAUCUCAGGUUUCAGCUCCUGCUGUCCUGAGCGAACUUGCCUGAUGCAGGGCUGUGCUGUGUCCAGAUGUUGCUGGGGCCUCACUUUUUCUCUUGGCUGGAGGUCCAAUUGCCAGAGCCUCCCACACUGCACAUACAAAGGUCUGAGCCCAGGGCAGCUUCUGGGGCCACUGCACAGGCCACCUGCUUGGGUUCCUCGGAGUUUAAUUUGAAAGUCUGGGUGUCUUAGGAUGAUGGUUAGGAACAUUGAAAAAUGGCUGCAAAUAGCCAAAUCAAACUUAAGAACCAGAUCUCUGCCAGAUUAAACAUUUUUGAAGCUUUUAAAAGUCAAUAUUCCUAGUGGCCACUGAGUUCCAGGCACACUGGUGCCCUUUACUGCCACAGCUGCUCACCUUGUCUGGCAAACUGGAGGGACCUCAGAAACUGGACUCCUGCAUGUCCUUGGGGGCGCAGCCCUGUGGUGCUCAGGCAGAGCUCUCAGGAGCCGGGGCACCUUGCUGUUCGCUGCUGUGUCGUCUUCUAAUGUGAGCUCAUCCACUGCUGCUGCAGCGUGGUGAUCAGGAGUCACAGACAAGAUCGGGGAUGGUGUGUGUGUGUGUGUGUGUGUGUGUGUGCACGUGUGUGUGGCUAAAUUAAGUCAUACUGUCAACCACACGUGAUCUCGUCUGAAACAGUGUUUGGAAGUGGGAACAGUUUUGUCCUGUAUGCUGAUGUGUCCAGAAUUUCAUUUAAUGAUAGACGGAAAAUGUGUGGUUACUGAAAACUGUAUAUGAUACAGAAUUUCAUAAGAGCCAUGCUGUUGGGCAAAGCAACUCUUUUUCAACCACUGCUCAUCAGUUUCUGUAGAGACAAAAACUCUGUACAUAUUUUGGAAUCUGAAGAAUCCUAUGUAAAUCAUUUGUUACUUAAGUCUGUGAAAAACAUAUUUCUUUGGAGGAAAAUGUAUGCAUUUAUAAGUGUUCCAUGGAAUCAGUUUUUAUUGUAUCGAUAUAAUUGUCUCUAAGUGUUGACUGUCUUCAUUGCAAUAUGAAAUUCAUUAAAAUGUCCAUGUUCCAUAAUUACUAUUAUAAAAGCUUUGUGUUAUUGGGAGUCUUAUUAUUUUUAUAGUUUUUCAUGUUUUGCUUUGGUGAAACAUUGUGAAUGACUAUAUAAACAUCACGAUGAGCUAGAAAUUGAACAAAUAUAAUACUGGUCACUCGAAAAAUUUUUAGACUUAAAAAGUCAGUUGUGUUUUGUGUCUGUCUCUUAUGCUAACAUUAAACAAUACAUAAUUA